GGAAUGCACAUUCUCAGCUUCCUCGGGGUCCUUCUGGGUCAGAAUCUCUGAGGUGAUGCCGAGCAUCUGUGAUGUGGCAAGCCUUCCGGAGAUUCUGACACACGCUUAAUUUUGAGAACCACUGAUCUGAGUCUUGGUGGGCAGCACCUGAGACAGGAGGGCAUGGAUGACACCUGAGAGACGGGAGGGCUCAACUCUACUGGCCGUAUGUGUGUGCAUGGUGUGGGGUGGUCGGGGAGGUCAGUGUGGGGAGGAUCUUUGCAUGCUCAGGAAAGCCAGGUGCCCAGCAGCUGUGUAAGUAACCAGGGGGCCAGCACUGCACAGGCCCUUGCCUGCCACCAGCCCUACUGACAUUCUUCCUAGAACAAGCAUGACGCAUGGCUUUUCUAGCACAUGGAAUCCUGGUCACACCACUGCUGACAGAAGAGGCUUCUGAUAAAGGCCAUUUCUCCCUUCCGUUUCUCCCCGAGCACCUCCUGCAUCCUAUCUCAUCGUGGGCCCGCGUCUGCCUUCCUGUUCUCGAAUCGCUGAGGCAGGAGUCAUGGCCCAGCACUAUUUUCCCUCUUCCAGUGGCAUUCUGGGGUUUUAUUCCGUGAACAUAAUUACCUUGUUUUUCUUCUUAAGCCAAUUCAGCUUAUUCAUGCCUCUUCCCUCAUGUUCCCACUGCCUUUCUCUUGUUUGGUUGCACAAUAUUCCAGAUAUUUUCUAUUGUCUCCUCUACCCCGUGGUUACAAAAUCAAACAGGACAAAACAGCUGUGCAUAGGCUGUGGAGGGGGCGCCUUGGGAGAAGCUGGGAUGGCCCCUUCCUUUCCACCCUGGCUCAGCUGCUGAUGGAAUGGAAGGUUUCCCGGAGAGGCAGCAGUCAGAGGAGUGGUCGGGGAGUCCCUGGGGCUGCCUUACGGGCUGGUUGCAGCGUUUCCUCUGCCACAGAGCUGCGAAUGCCAAGGUAAACAUAUGUUUUGAGAUAAAGUGGAAACCCCAGGAGGUUUUCAUCCUAGAAGAGGAAGCAAUAAGACAGUCACGUGUUGGACCAAGGAGUCGUUUUCCCCCAAACCCAGCUUUGCGCACCCUGUGUGGGAAAGUUGGAGGGAAUUGGAAAAGCAGGGAUUAUGGAUGGGGCCAAUGAGACAGGUCACAGAGUGCAAGAAGGGGCUUGAAGAGGCAGCUGGCUCUGCUCCUUCCCAGUACAUGACUGUGGGCCCGUAUCCUUCAUCUUCCUUACUGGUAGCAUCAGGACUGGACUACCAUAUGCCAGGCGGUGUCCUGGGGAUCAAAUGUGGAACGAACGUAAAGCAUUUGGCACAGUGCCUGUCUGCCUCGUGGAAAACGGUGGCUGCGAGUUUUAUUAGCUCUUUCUAGUAGUCGACUGGCUGUUGUACUGUCUUUGUUUCUGAAGGUGCCCGAUACACACUUCUAAUCCAUCUGCAAUGCCUGUCCACUCCACCUUCAAAAUAUAUUCCCGAUCAGACCUCUUUGAACCACACCGGCCAUUCCUCCCACGGUCCAGGCCUGUGCUGCCCUUGCCUGCUGGGUCUCCUCCCUGCCACGGAGCUUCCUCUUCAACAGUUUUUUCUUACAUGACAGGCAGAGGGUUACUUUUAAGCCCCAAACCAGAUCCUGUGGGUUCCCUGCUCAGAAUCUUCUAACAGCUUCUGAAGACACUUAAGAUAGAACUGACAGAACAGUAGGGCGCCCAGGACAUGUGGCCCAGGGUUCUCCUGCCAACCUCUCUUCCUGGUGCUCACUCCCGGGAAGCCACCUCUGCCUCAGCCUCCUCCUUCCCUUGCCAGGCUCGCCUCCAUCUCCAGCUUGGCACCCAUAAUCUUCCUGGGCCCGGCACACUCUCCCCCUGACAUCUCCAUAACUCGCUCUCUUCCCACCGUUAGGUCUCUGUUCAAGAGCAUCUCCUCAGAGAGACAGAAGCGGCCUCUCCAUUUAGUUUUCAGUUAUUGCUGGACAUUGCGUGUUUCUCUGUCCUUUGCCUGUGUGAUGGGAACACAGACCCAGCAUCUUCACGCCCCCACUGUGUUCCCAUCGACUGCACAUGAGAGAUGCAAUGAGUUUUAUUAAUACAACUGAUUUCACUAAUCAAAACAUUUAAACAUAUUUUUCGAGCUAAUAAAACUUGCCCAUCUGCCCUGUAAUGGUAUUUGGAGAGAUGAAGGACUCAGGACACAGUGCUAGGGAAUUUCCAGUUCCGUUUGUGACUCCUGUUGACCAUCUUAAAAAACGGCGACUUAUAUGACUUUUCAGUGAGUUAAUCUUCUGUAUUUUUUUUUUUUUUGAGAUGGAGUUUCACUCUUGUUGCCCAGGCUGGAGUGCCAUAGCGCAAUCUUGGCUCACUGCAACCUCUGCCUCCUGGGUUCAAGCGAUUCUCCUGCCUCAGCAUCCUGAGUACCUGGGGUUACAGGCGUCCGUCCCCACGCCCGACUCAUUUUUUGUCUUUUUAGUAGAGACGGGAUUUCACCAUGUUGGACAGACUAGUCUGGAGCUCCUGACCUCAGGUGAUCCACCAUCCUUAGCCUCCCAAAGUGCUAGGAUUAUAGGCGUGAGCCACCGCGCCUGGCCUCUUCUGUACCAUUUAACACCCUUUUUUAUCUGUGCAGUAGGUAGAGGAACCUCAGAUUCAACCCAUAUUUACUGAAUACCUCAAUACUCUCCCUUUAAAAACUGACAUGGGGCAGUGGACCUUGGAGAUUCACGGCGUCCCUCCUCUGGGGUGGAGUGUGAGAUGGCCUCUGCCUGUGAGACCUGCUGCAGUGGAAUCGAUCUGCGCCGCCUCCAACCGAGACCUGAAGACGCAAAUUCCAUGGUGUCAGUGUGAAGAACUGUGAGGAGGCAGUGAGAGGAGGGCCUGGGCAGGGUGUCCCGCAUGGGCCAAAUGGCCAAGUCACUCCUGCUAUUCAGGAAACAGGCUUGGUGGGGUCACAUAACUUGUCCACUGACACAGGAAGACUUCAGUUCUGGUGACUUGGUGUCCUGCACUUACCGCCAGAGCCCUUUGUGGCUGCCCAGCGUGAGACCUUCGUUGCCAUCAAAAGGAGGGGAAGGGAAUAGCCGAUUGGGCAUCUACGUCCCACCAGCGUGUUUCAUGUUAAGAAGAAGGUGGGUUUACUGGGAGGAUGUGUCACCUCUCUGCAUGACUUGAUGUGAGUCUGGGAACACCAAGUGUUCAUUCCAUGUCUGGCACUAUUUUCAUCUCCAUCAGGCUUUCAGAGCCCAGGGAUGAUGGGUCGAUACCCGGGACUUGAACCUCACAUCUGCCUUGAGGGGAAGGAGAGGAGUUGGGGAGGUGCUGGCAGGGGGAAGCCCACCUCCCACCCUGGCUCCAUGCUGCAGGCAGGUGUCCUGCCCGGGUGGAUUGGCUUCCGCUGCUAGGCCAGGGUUAGCCUAGUUCUGGUGAGGAAAGUUCUCCAUUCUGAGCCUUGUAAUGAAAUCUAGAGCUGCCUCUGGCCAGGUAUCCCCAACCCAACCCAAUUUUUCUGCCUAUCUCAUUGGAAGUGUCAAUUUCUUUAUUACUUCAGCUGAGGGAAAACAGGUCUUGACACUAAGACAAUUCAAGUGGGGGCAAGGUCGCCGUGAUUCAUUUUUGUUACUCUGUUGAGUUCUAGAGUAAGUAUAAUUCACAAGUAAAAUGAAGGUUCAGGAAUUAGAUGUGGAGACUAAGGACGAUGCCAAGAUUUAUUCUAUGUCUGUGCUCAGCCUAAAUUGGGCUCAAAAGGAAGAAAAAGGAUGAGGAAUUACUACACAUUAUUCGCUUCUCCUGAGGAUGACGGUAAGAUGACCUAAUACAAUCAGGGGCGAAUCUGAGGCCAGAAAAUGCAUACCCAAAGCUCAGAAGGAGGCAACAGACCAUUGAGACCCUUUUGGACAAGACUGAGUGAGUUCAAGAAAAACCGGCACCUGACCAGCCAAGUAGGUGAUUCCAAACUCACUCCUGCCCUGAGAACCCUUGGACACACCAGGAAAUUACACAUUGUGUGACAUCAGCUUGGGAGAAGGCCUUUUUAUCCCAAGUCUGAUCAGCUUCUGUAACACUUAGAAAAAGGAUUUGAUUACAGGCGGUCAGUGGAGAAGGAAACAGAUCACCAUCAGUAACUGGCCAGGAUUCUUUUCUUCCUCAUUCAUGGUCCCUGUCAGGCCAGCGAAUGGGAGGUGCUGAUGUUCCUGUGGGAAGGCAGUUAUCCCCUGUGGAUUCCAGUGGCUGGUUUAUGAAAUAAGAAGCUUAUGCACACUGGGAAUUGUCUUUAAUGAAAUGAGAAUUAGCCAGAGAGUUAGACAUAGGGGUCAUUGCCAAGAGGAAUUAACACUGAAGCCUCAAUUAAAAUUUCCACUGGAUUAUCUGAUAAGUAGUUGUGCCUUUGGUAUUUUAUUGUCUUUGACAAAUGGCAUGAGUUCAGAAUUUGAAGCAACGUAGGCCAUAACAUAACACGGUCCUGAAAAUAAUGAGGCACACCAUUGCUAGAUACAAAGUACUUAAAUUCCCUGAUGGAAGUAUUUAUUUUAAAGACUGCUUUGGAUUAUCUUCCUCCCAGGAUGUGCAGGCGCUCUCUCUGUGUUCUGAUGGGGUUGCCAACUUCACAAUUCCUUUUGGUGCCAACAGAGUUCUCAGCACCAGGUGGAAAGGGUGGCUGCCUUCCAAGACAUACCUUGCUUUAUUGCUAAUCCCUCUGUCUCCUCCCCCCGUGGGCUGUUCUUGUCCCCUGGCUGCUGGGAGACAGAGUGAUGGCUUCCUAAUUGGGUCCCCAGGCAGUCCCAACACCUGUUUCAGGAGGUGUUUGGUAUCAACAGUGGACAUGUUUCCGAAGCUAGGUGUGUGUGUGUUUAAAUUCAUUUUUAUAAUUUUGUUUCUUCCAAGCAUUGUCGUUACCCACUAUUGGUGCCUUCAUUUAAACAAUAAAUGCUUUCAUUCAAAAUGCAAUACUUCCUAAGCUUUUGCUGAGUGAUCAAACCCGAAAAAAGUGUUAAAUGCCAGUCACUCCCAUCUCAACCCAGUGGUCAGGCCUGAGAUAGCUGUUAUGAAGAUGCCUCAGGACAAUUAGACUUUUCAGGAACUUUUCGGCUAUGAUGCCAUUGCAAUUUGCAGACCAUCCCAGUCUAACCCCGUUUCCUCCACCCCUUGCUCUCCUUGCACCAUUGCUGGCCUCAGAUCCCUCCCUGCUGUGAGGUUUGGAAUUAGCUCGUGUGUCUAUGGCAUGGAUGACUUCUCCUCCAACUCUGUACCAGCCAGCAUCUGGAAAGAGUUAUACACAGGAAUCUGUUACUAUCUAGCCUGCCCUCAGCCCUGGAUGCGCAUCUGAUGUGGAGACCCACUGGACGCUCUGUAGAAUGUGGAGUUCUCUUUGAAGGUACCACAAAGAUAGGGGUCUGCAAGUGUGGCUUUCGUGCACCGCGGGUGUCAUUCGUGACGUGUUUGUGCUCUUCUGCAAGCCCAAACUGCGGAGAAAGUUUAACUGAGAAAACCACUUAUUCUGAGUUGUCUUCUCAGUUAAUAUGCCCCUGGUUAUGUUUAAGUGCCCGGUGUUGGUUAUGCUCGUGCAGCUUGGCCAGGAAACUUCUAGGACUUCAGCAUGGGAUGGGUGGUUGGCAGUGGGGGCAGAGUGAGUUGGAGCUAGUUGAUGUGCUGUGGGUGCAUCCUCCUUAGCUGUGAGGGAGGCCAACACAGGCAGGCUUUCCCUGCACUGAUCAUCUCAGGUGACUGUGUGGCAAUUUCCUGCUGGUCAGGGAAGGUGCUGUGGCCUUUCAUCUUGGCUCUGUGUCCACCUGCUCACUGGAGCUCCAUACUUCACCACUGCAAGAGAGUUGCCCUUGCGUUCUCUGUCUACACUUCAAAGGAAGAUGUUUGCAUUUGGUCAGGGAGAGGGAACUUUGCAGUUAGUUCUCCUGAGGCUCUGUGGGUGUUUUGUUGUGGGAGGAGGCGUGUCAGCAUCUUCAACGGAUCAUGUGACCUUUGAGUGGUUGCCUCUGGGACAUCAUAUGAUUCUUUGAGGUCAACAGAGGGUGGAUCCUUUGGACUGCAGCCAGGAGACUGGGUCCUUUUUAGUUUAGCGGGACCAGCCUUGCUGUGGUUCUCAGUCCAGAGAGAAGACUUCCUGAAUGUGAAGUGAGCAUCCAGGUCAACAGGCAGAACCACUGUGCGUCAUAGAACAGAAGCCACUGAAAUAAGAGUGAUUGUCCCAUGGACCAAGACAUCAGCAGAGAUUUGUAAGGCAGGAAUUUGCAAGGGAAGGCAUCAGCAACACUCAUGUUUCACGUCAGAGUUGCAGGGCAGGAUAUUAGAUAAGAGGCCUGGGAGUCCAGUCAAUGGUCACUUCUGUCAAUGUGGGGAGGGGGUGGGGAGAGCUACCUAGGAGGGAGAGUGAUUCAUAGCCUGAAACCAUCUUUGCGUCCUAUUUGCAAGCUGUUGGGUUGUGCAGGACUUAAAGCUGUGCUGGCUCCUCAGCACCUGCAGUGUCAGUGGUGAGCUACUCUGUUGGGGUCUUCAGGGAUACUCCAUAAGAACCAUCUUCCCCUCCCAGGCUUGGAACCAGUGGUAGUCACAGUGUCUGUGAGCAUUACUACCAAGGAAGCUGAUUGGAGAAGGGGGCCCAAAUGUCACUGAAUGUUUCACCUUAGAAUGAUCCAAUUUGCUCCCUGAAAUUUAACGGAAGCACUAUCCAACUUCUCUUCUGCAACUGUCACAGACAGGACCGCAGGGCAAUGGCCCCCUCGUAGAGGCAGGUGACACUGUGGGUGGUGAGCCCACCACAGGGCCCCAUCCUCCCACAGGUAGGCAGGGAGAGCUGGGGUUGGGGGGCUAGUGAGCAGGCCAGCUCCUUCCCCCAGACCAUUGGACAGACAAGUCACCUGCCCUUGCCAGGCAGAGCAUUGCUGUGGCAGACCUCACUCUGCAUGGAAACACGAGGGGUAGAGAAUAGGAGUUCUCCAAGAGCAUGCCAAGUGUGGCAUUUGACGUUUCAUGCCCUCACCUGCCUGUGUCUGUUCAGCGCUCUCUCGUGGUCUCUCACAUGUCCACUUGGGCUGGGUCUGUGUCCUCAUCCUGCCCUAAAUGUACCUGCUCACUCUCACCCUCGAGUUUUCCUUUUCUCCUCGGUCCAGUCCCUCUUUCAGUUAGUUCAUUAAUGCACUAAUUGAUCAAUAAUGAAUUCAGCAGUGUUCAUGAGCCUCUGUACCUGUCAGGCUUUGCGUAUGGUACCAGUAUUAUAGUGAUGUGCAAAGCAGAUGAGAUUCCUGCCUUCAGAACACUUACAGUCUAAUCAGAGUGACAGGCAUAAAAGAACUUGUCAUACAAAUAGAUAUGAUGAUAAACUGGGCCAGGUUUCUUGAAUGCAGAGGUCACGCGCUGGAUGGUGUCAAAGUAGACUGUUCUGAGGCCUUUCGGAGAUGGUAACAUCAAGGCUAGGAUCCGAACUGUGAGAAGGAGUCAGCCAUGUAAAGAUUUCGGGAAAGAGCGUGUAGGUGAGGAGAUGGCCCCUUCUGAAAGCCUUGAAGCAAGAAAGAGUUUGGAGCAUUUGAGGAACAUGAAGGAGGCCCAGUAGUGAGAAAUAAGGCAGGGCUGUAUCUGCAGGGCCUUGAGGGCUCCACAAAGCGUCGUGGAUUUUAUCUGAGUGUCGGGAUUCAUCAUCAAAGAGCUAUGGGCAGAUGACGUGGCCAUGUUUACUGCAGUGGGAGCAAGGUCAGGAAUGAAAGCCGUUGCUCUAAGAUAACAGUGGGUUUGGAAGGUAUUGCUAGUUGUGGACUUAGCAGCCAUGCCCCUCUCUUAUACAUUGCUGGGCUGUGUGCCCACCCUCAGGUGAUGAAGCCGGUCACGACAGUCCAUUCCUUUUCCUGGAUAAUCACUUACCUGGUCUCCCUUGCAGCAGUGGCUGUGCAAUCCCACGUAGCCCAGGGAAAUCUAAGCAAAGGCCUGCUGGCAGCCUCAGAGAAAGGUUUUCCACCCUGGGAAGCUACUGUGUGAGGACAGUGCUUAGGGCUUCUGCAGCUGUCUUGGGACCAUGAGGGAAAGGCCAGGAGGACCACAGAUCUGUCCAUCCAGCGAUGUGCCAUCACUGGGCUGCCUGAUCAAUCCAGGGCCGCCUGCCUCUCCAGACUUCUGUGUUGAGCAAUGGUGUCUCGUCUCUGAUUAAACCAUUGUUUUCUAUUACUUGCGGCCAAGUGUACAGUCAUUUAGGGGAGAUAAAGAAAAGUGGGUGGAUCUGAGAUCUCCAUAUUGACAUGACUUAGUAAUGAAUUGGAGGUGGAAUGGGGAGGAUUGGAGGGGGUAGUGAGGAUUUCUGAUGUGGGUGGGAAAGACAGAGGAUCUCAGUUUUGCUCCCAGCAGAACAGACAGUGGUUAUUUGGGUUGAGGUGAACCCACUUUGAUUUGGAGCUGGGCCUGAGUCAGAGGUUUGACUUUAGCCUGUGAGAAAUCCAGGUGGAAGUGUUCAGGAGAUGGUUGAAACACAGAUCUGGAUUUGAACAGCGAGAUCUGGCUGAGGGGGCACUCGGGGUUCAUCAGUGCUCAGAGGUGGGGCCUGAGGCUGUGGGUAGGGUUUCAUCAUGGUGGGAGGGAGGAGAGCCAGGAGAGGCCCAGGUGGGAACAGCUACUGCUUUUCUUAUUCUGCCCAGGAUCUUUAUUUUAGUCUCUUUUGAAAUGAUGGACGUCAUAUAUUUGUCACUUAAUUGCAUCAAAUCACAAAUAUUAGGCUGACUCACAUGAAAUUGUCAUUUUUCUAGAUCAGAACAGUUGAUUAUUAGCAAUUGUGUAGGACUCAACCUAAUAGCUGUUGUUACCAACUGUGUACCAGAUACUGUAUUAGAUCAAACCAACCAAUGAAUUCUCACUUAUUUUCUGUUUAAAUUUAAUCCCAUCACUCCCAUGUAUAAAACUCACCAUUGGUUUCUCUGCAUCCACAAGGUAAAAUGCCAACCGAGAUCAUCCUCUGAGGUCUUUUAUGGUCCAUCUCCACCCAUGUUUGCUGAAAGCCCCUGCACUCUCCUUUCCAGGCAUAUCAAGCCCAGAUCUGCAAAUGCAGUGAGAGAGUUACAGGAUUUCUCCAGAAUCCCAUUUCCACUCGGUGUCUAGUCUUGGCCUCUGCAUGUGUCCAUAUCACGAGUUCAGUUUCACGGAAAAGCCUCUCUUCACUUCGUGGUCUGGAUGUGGAUGGUAUACAGUUGUGCUUCUGAUUGUAUUAUGGUCCCUCAAAACCACAUCUGAUUAUGUGCCUGGACAUUUGGGGUUUCAGGCCUGAAGGGCCAAGCCUCCUUUUCCCCCGGCUGACUCCUGCUUAUCUUUGGAGGCGUAACUCAUGUCAUGACUGCUGGGUAGUCUGUGGCCUCCCUGGGAACUCCAAGGACCCAGAUCCUCCACUGUCUUGGAACCUCUCUGGCUGGGCUGACAUCACCCUGGAGCAGCACCCAGAACACAGACCAUGACUGCUCUGAGGACGGAAUGGCACAGAGGCCAUGACUGCUGUAAGGACUGAAUGGGCACAGAGGCCGUGACUGCUGUAAGGACUGAAUGGCACAGAGACCGUGACUGCUGUAAGGACUGAAUGGGCACAGAGACCGUGACUGCUGUAAGGACUGAAUGGGCACAGAGGCUGUGACUGCUAUAAGGACUGAAUGGCACAGAGGCUAUGACUGCUAUAAGGACUGAAUGGCACAGAGGCUAUGACUGCUAUAAGGACUGAAUGGCACAGAGACCGUGACUGCUGUAAGGACUGAAUGGCACAGAGACCGUGACUGCUGUAAGGACUGAAUGGCGCAGAGGCCGUGACUGCUGUAAGGACUGAAUGGCACAGAGACCGUGACUGCUGUAAGGACAGAGUGGGCACAGAGGCCGUGACUGCUGUAAGGACAGAAUGGGACAGAGGCUAUGACUGCUAUAAGGACUGAAUGGCACAGAGACCAUGACUGCUCUAAGGACUGAAUGGGCACAGAGACCGUGACUGCUGUAAGGACUGAAUGGGCACAGAGACCGUGACUGCUGUAAGGACUGAAUGGCACAGAGACCGUGACUGCUGUAAGGACUGAAUGGCACAGAGACCGUGACUGCUGUGAGGACUGAAUGGCACAGAGACCGUGACUGCUAUAAGGACUGCAUGGCACAGAGGCCGUGACUGCUGUAAGGACUGAAUGGCACAGAGACCGUGACUGCUGUAAGGACUGCAUGAAUGGGCACAGAGGCCGUGACUGCUUAAGGACUGCAUGAAUGGCUGCUGCUGGGGUUUCUUUCUGAACCAUCGGGGAAGCUCCCCCAAGUCCCCUUUGUCCCCUCUUGGGUCCUAGUUUGAGCCAUGUGCUGGCACUCAGUUAUUUUAACGAAACCAUAUACAUUUUUGACAUGACAGAGGAAUGAUUUGUAUGUUCUUCCCCAACUCUUAAAAAAAGAAUUAAAAAGGAUCUUUUAGCCCUUUUAUAAAAUCUUUGCUAUGUUCCUCAGAAGGCUUUUACCAAGAUGGUUAAGUAUGUUUCCAAUCUUGGAGCAAUAGCAGCUGCAUGUUUUGCUGCAACUGGAGGAAAGUAUAUUUCUUGUGGAAUUCAGCCUACAAAGGCAGGUUCCCCAUGGCCGUGAAAUUGGUGGUGAGUAACAGGGAGGACUUGGUUCUAGCAAGGCAGUGAUGAGCAAGGCAGCCUCGUGGAUCCAUGACACAUCCAGGGGCUCAUUACUUCUGGGUGCUCAUGGGUCCAGAUGGAAUGCAGGUGGUUAAGUCUGUGGGGUUCUUGAAGUUGCCUGACAAGCUUCGCAGCUUCCUUUGCUGCUUCUACCCUUAAAACCUGUGGGUGGCCCUGUUUUGACAAAGAGUAGGACUGUUGAGAGCCUUGGGGUUGGCCCCGGAGGCUCUCUCUGGAAGUGGAGGGAUUCCCCUUUCCUAGAAUGUCAAUGCCUGGUGCGGUCAGUGCAGGACAAAGAGUGUUCUGUGUCUCUGUAAGGCUGCUUGGGAGAUGUAAUCCUAGGAGAAGGUUACAGCAGAUCAGAGAGAGUACUGGGGAAGCAGUGACCUUUCCUCGCCUUUGCACUGGGGGUGAAGAACGAGGACCUUAUAAUAAAGGAGAAUAUUUUGCCUCUGCACAAUGGCAAGCGUUUUCACUCUCAAACCAAAUCCCUUUUGAGGUUUUUUUGUUUUCUCUUUGAAAUCUUGUGAUGACUGAGUAAUUUAUGAUGUAGUAACCUUGUCUGUAUCUCAAUUCUUUUACCCUUGUAAACAUCUGCUGCAAAAAUCACAAAUGGCUGGCUGCAAAGGAGGAAGUUACCGCCCACCAAAGCCUCCCCAUCCUGUUCCCUCUCCCUCCCUGGUAUAUCUGUACCCCCCACCCUCCUGUACUCACUGCACUUAGACAAUUGCAUUUGCUCUGUCUCUGCUCUGUAAUCGCCAAGUACACUCCAAAGGCGGUGGGCAGUGUGGACAUCCCCACCAUGAUGGUUAAUACCGAGUGUCAACUUGACUGGAUUGAAGGAUACAGAAUAUUAAUCCUGGGUGUGUCUGUGUGGGUGUUGGCAAAAGAGAUUAACAUUUGGGUCAGGGGGCUGGGGAAGGCAGAUCCACCCUUAAUCUGGUGGGCACAAUCUAAUCAGCUUCCAGUGAAUAUAAAGCAAUAAGAAAAACGUGAAAAGGAGAGAUGGGCCAAGCCUCCCAGCCUACGUCUUUCUCCCAUGCUGGAUGCUUCCUGCCAUUGAACACUGGACUCCAAGUUCUUCAGCUUCGGGACUCGGACUGCUUCUCCUUGCUCCUCAGCUUGCAGACAGCCUAUUGGGGGACCUUGUGAAUGUAUAAGUUAAUACUUAAUAAACUCCAUAUAUAUACACACAUAUAUACACACACACACAUAUAUAUACACCCACACAGACACACCCAGGAUAUAUAUAUGUGUGUGUGUAUAUAUAUAUACACAUACAUGUGUAUAUAUACACUAUAUGUAUAUACAUAUAUACAUGUAUAUAUACACAUAUAUGUGUGUGUGUCUGUGGGUGUGUGUGUGUGAAGUUCUAUCUCUCUAAGAAAACCCUAAUACACGCACAUAUGUGGGCCACCAGGACAAGAGUCACUGUGAUUCUCAUUCAUCUCCUCUUCUCAGAGUGAGUCCCUGCCUUCUUUGCCCUGCUCCUGGCUUCCUGGGAAGGCAAUAUCCAGCUUCUGCCCCCGUGAGAUGAGCUCAGGGCCAGUAUAGAGAGAGAGAGCACUUUGAAACAUGGUUAUAUACUUCAUGCAGAAGUAGCAAACUAGUUACUCAGGCUGCAUCUGGUCUCAAACAUGUUUUGUUUAAUAUUUUCUUAUUAGUCUUCUAAUACUGAAAAAAAAGAGUCAGUGCUUUUUCCUAAGAAAGGAAACAACUGACUCUUUGGUGGCUUUGGAAAAAUCUGGCACCUCCAGGCGCACAUCCCCACGUGGCAGCAGUGAGCUGGAGCUAAGGCGUGGCUGUCCCCUUUAGACAGUUUCCAGUUUGCCUUAGUCCCCACCAUGUCCUUUUGUCUCCCUCCCCUGAUGCUAAGUGACAGGUGCCUCUCGUCCUCACAUUGUGCUGUGACUUUCCUUGUGGUGCAGUAAGAGAAAACUGAAAUGUUCCUGCACCCGCAUCUUUAUCAAAAGUGGGAAAAUGGAAAAUAGGGUGAGAGCGCUGAGUGUUUCAAGGGAAGAAAUGUGAAAGCCUAGCUUUCUUCGUAGAAUUAAAUCCCAGGAAACACCCCUUUGUGAUUUGAAUGCCAGCAAAGUGUGUCCAUGUUAGAAGAACACAAUUCAAAAGACCAUUGGAAGGGUGCCUGCCUCCCCCUUAGGCUUCCUGCCUGGUCCGUAGCAUUCGAGUUGGUCACUCUUACUCUGAAAAGGCCAUUUCUUAAUGGCAGCCACGUUGGCAUCAUGGGCGGAACAGUUUCUUGUUGUGCAGGAGUGUCUGCCAUACUGCAGAGCGUUGGCCAUUUUGGCCUCUGUCCAGGCAUGACCCCUCAGUCGUGUAACAACUCCUGCCCCCAAUAUUUCCAGACUUUUCCGGUGGAGAAGUCCAGCCCUCCAGGGAUGUUGGAUGGUAGAUGUUUGUGUCCUAGGAUGGACUGGGCCAGAGGACCUGGCCCCAAGCUGUGUGCUUGGUUCAGGGGGGACACGGAGGCCACCCAGGUGCACAUGUUGCCCAGGUUCUGUGUUCUCCCAGUGCAGCACUGAGCCAGUCAGAUCUGCCUCAUUCCAGGCAGGGCUGCCCGGGUUUUCAGAAGAUGCGGCAGAACAAAGCCACGCUUAUUUGAAUCAUGUCUUUCUGUUCAGACGUGCUGUGGCCCCUUUCAUCUACGUGGGCUGGCAGGAGCAUCUGGUCUGCCCGCCAGCAUGGUAUUAAGAGCCAUCCACAGCCGGAUGCCAGGACUUAAGGCAGAGAACUGUCUGCAUGAAGCGGCACCUCCUCGGUGCUUACCUGGCACUCUGCUUCCUUUCUGGGAUCUAUUUUGGUGUCUGUACCACAGUCCACCUUGUUCUGUGUGGAUGAGUCUUCCGUAGCUACAAGGAAAUAGUCACGUUGCAAAUUGCUGGGUUGCAGCUGAUCCCGCUCCUGCAGUGGUGAGAUCAGACUGCCAUGAAAGCACUCUUAAGGCUAAGGCGUGACUUCGUUUAAUAAAAUGGUUUGCACAAAUCCACCUGGUUGACUGGGUCACAGACUGUGUGCCUCUGUGUGAUGAUGGCCUCGAGGCCCUCAGGUGAUGCCUGCACAGCUUCUCAGAGACCCCAGGCGGCCUCCGGCAGAGGUGUCAGCCCGAGAGCAGAAGGAGUGUGCAAGGCCGGGCCAACCCCGAGCACAGGCAGAAGUCAACAAGCAGCCUUAUUUCAGGCCCUGUUAAGAGGAGCAGAAGUUCUUGGAAGUAAAUGGAAUUCUGGAUAAUUUCACACCAGCUCUCAGACCACCCGGCAAACCUGUCCCAGAGGCACUCUUCAUCCAUUUACAGAAACAGCCUUCGGGAAGAACUUGAGACCCAUGAGAAUGACGUGGGAGUUUGCACACGUGCCAAGGCUUCAGCAAGUGGUCAUGACUGACUUGGCGUAUGGCUGAUUUUAGAGCAAGGGAAGACUCAUGUAUUGUAAUUAAAGGGAGGUGGAAGUAUAUUAGAACUUCCGUUAUCUCAGGGCAGAGUUUGUUACUCCAAAAGAACAAUAGGUAUUAUAGCAUAAAAUUUCCCAACGGCUGACCAUUCAGAACAACUUUAUUCACAUAUAGUUUGUACAAAUAGUGCAGAUUACCACCUUAUAUGAGUGUAUGAGCUGUCCACUACUGUAGCAAAAUUUUUUCUCUCCUUAAAACACACACACAUAUGCUAUGCGGGACUCAAGAGUCUACAGGCAGUGAGACAAAUUCUGUCACUGUUAAAAAAAAAAAAAGUGAAGUUUAUUGGCGUAGCUUUAGUGGGCAUUAAACAUUUCCAGCAUAUUUUUGUGUAUUUCAAGAGGCUAAUUGUGUUAUUUAAUUGAGAAGAUUUGUGAGCAUCUUGUAGGUGUCACUGUUUAAAAAAAAAACACAUAAGCGUUUGCCCGUCAAACUGGUGGUAUUAAAUUGGAAAUCAGGAAGCAUGUUCCCAGUUCCUCAAGAAAUUAAACAUAGAGUUAUUGUAUAGGCAGCUGUUUCACUCCUAGGUAGGUACCCAAGAGAAUUGGAAACAUAGGUCCGUGCAGAAACUUGUACGUGAAUAAUCACAGUCGCAUUAUCCGUCAUAGUCCCAAUGUAGAAACUACCCAAGUGUCCAUCAGUUGAUGAAUGGAUGCCUCAGUUGUGGAAUAUCCAUGCAAUGGAAUGUUAUUUGGCAAUAAGAAGUACUAACAUUACAUGCUGUGACAUGGAUGACCCUUGACAACGUUAUGCUAAAUGAAAGAAGCCAGUCACAAAAGGCCGCAUAUCGUGUGAUUCCAUUAGGUGAAGUGUCCAGAAGAGGCGAGUGCACAGAGACAAAGUAGAUUAGUGGGUGCCAGGGGCUCGGGGAGGAGGAAGUGGGCUGUGAUCUCACAUCUUUCAUCACCCUAGCUAUAAGAGUGAUGAAAAUCUUCUCGAAUUAUGUCAUGAUGAUGGCUGCACAACUUUGAGAAAGUACUAAAACCACUGAAGCAUAUACUUCAAAGGGGUGAACUUAAUGGUGUGUGAAUUAUAUCCUAAUACAAAAAUAGCGAGGUAGAGCAGAUGGGAGAAAAUAUUAUCAGUUGUUACAUCUAAGUGGAGGGACUAGAGCUGAUCAUGUUACUGUUAUUUCUACUUUUCUGUGUUUGAAUAUUUUCACAGUGAAGCGUUCGGGGGAAAGAAGAAAGGUGGCAAAGACAAGAAAAGCAUAUGCUUCCGCUGCCACCCCACUUAGGAUGGAUUUAUUUCAGUUCAACAAAAAAGACACAGGAGGCGCUGGUGACAUCUCGGGCUACUGAAUGUUUCCCACUUUUCGAGGGAAUUGCUUACUUAGGAGGUGUGUGCAGUGCUAAGAGGAAGUGUGUGCUUGCCGAAGACAAUGGUCUCAAUUUGGCCUUUACCAUCGCCCAUGAGCUGGGCCACAACUUGGGCAUGAACCACGACGAUGACCACUCAUCUUGCGCUGGCAGGUCCCACAUCAUGUCAGGAGAGUGGGUGAAAGGCCGGAACCCAAGUGACCUCUCUUGGUCCUCCUGCAGCCGAGAUGACCUUGAAAACUUCCUCAAGUCAAAAGUCAGCACCUGCUUGCUAGUCACGGACCCCAGAAGCCAGCACACAGUACGCCUCCCGCACAAGCUGCCGGGCAUGCACUACAGUGCCAACGAGCAGUGCCAGAUCCUGUUUGGCAUGAAUGCCACCUUCUGCAGAAACAUGGAGCAUCUAAUGUGUGCUGGACUGUGGUGCCUGGUAGAAGGAGACACAUCCUGCAAGACCAAGCUGGACCCUCCCCUGGAUGGCACCGAGUGUGGGGCAGACAAGUGGUGCCGCGCGGGGGAGUGCGUGAGCAAGACGCCCAUCCCGGAGCAUGUGGACGGAGACUGGAGCCCGUGGGGCGCCUGGAGCAUGUGCAGCCGAACAUGUGGGACGGGAGCCCGCUUCAGGCAGAGGAAAUGUGACAACCCCCCCCCUGGGCCUGGAGGCACACACUGCCCGGGUGCCAGUGUAGAACAUGCGGUCUGCGAGAACCUGCCCUGCCCCAAGGGUCUGCCCAGCUUCCGGGACCAGCAGUGCCAGGCACACGACCGGCUGAGCCCCAAGAAGAAAGGCCUGCUGACAGCCGUGGUGGUUGACGAUAAGCCAUGUGAACUCUACUGCUCGCCCCUCGGGAAGGAGUCCCCACUGCUGGUGGCCGACAGGGUCCUGGACGGUACACCCUGCGGGCCCUACGAGACUGAUCUCUGCGUGCACGGCAAGUGCCAGAAAAUCGGCUGUGACGGCAUCAUCGGGUCUGCAGCCAAAGAGGACAGAUGCGGGGUCUGCAGCGGGGACGGCAAGACCUGCCACUUGGUGAAGGGCGACUUCAGCCACGCCCGGGGGACAGUUAAGAAUGAUCUCUGUACGAAGGUAUCCACAUGUGUGAUGGCAGAGGCUGUUCCCAAGUGUUUCUCAUGUUAUAUCGAAGCUGCCGUCAUUCCUGCUGGAGCUCGGAGGAUCCGUGUGGUGGAGGAUAAACCUGCCCACAGCUUUCUGGCUCUCAAAGACUCGGGUAAGGGGUCCAUCAACAGUGACUGGAAGAUAGAGCUCCCCGGAGAGUUCCAGAUUGCAGGCACAACUGUUCGCUAUGUGAGAAGGGGGCUGUGGGAGAAGAUCUCUGCCAAGGGACCAACCAAACUACCGCUGCACUUGAUGGUGUUGUUAUUUCACGACCAAGAUUAUGGAAUUCAUUAUGAAUACACUGUUCCUGUAAACCGCACUGCGGAAAAUCAAAGCGAACCAGAAAAACCGCAGGACUCUUUGUUCAUCUGGACCCACAGCGGCUGGGAAGGGUGCAGUGUGCAGUGCGGCGGAGGGGAGCGCAGAACCAUCGUCUCGUGUACACGGAUUGUCAACAAGACCACAACUCUGGUGAACGACAGUGACUGCCCUCAAGCAAGCCGCCCAGAGCCCCAGGUCCGAAGGUGCAACUUGCACCCCUGCCAGUCACGGUGGGUGGCAGGCCCGUGGAGCCCCUGCUCGGCGACCUGUGAGAAAGGCUUCCAGCACCGGGAGGUGACCUGCGUGUACCAGCUGCAGAACGGCACACACGUCGCUACGCGGCCCCUCUACUGCCCGGGCCCCCGGCCGGCGGCAGUGCAGAGCUGUGAAGGCCAGGACUGCCUGUCCAUCUGGGAGGCGUCUGAGUGGUCACAGUGCUCUGCCAGCUGUGGUAAAGGGGUGUGGAAACGGACCGUGGCGUGCACCAACUCACAAGGGAAAUGCGACGCAUCCACGAGGCCGAGAGCCGAGGAGGCCUGCGAGGACUACUCAGGCUGCUACGAGUGGAAAACUGGGGACUGGUCUACGUGCUCGUCGACCUGCGGGAAGGGCCUGCAGUCCCGGGUGGUGCAGUGCAUGCACAAGGUCACAGGGCGCCACGGCAGCGAGUGCCCCGCCCUCUCGAAGCCUGCCCCCUACAGACAGUGCUACCAGGAGGUCUGCAACGACAGGAUCAACGCCAACACCAUCACCUCCCCCCGCCUUGCUGCUCUGACCUACAAAUGCACACGAGACCAGUGGACGGUAUAUUGCCGGGUCAUCCGAGAAAAGAACCUCUGCCAGGACAUGCGGUGGUACCAGCGCUGCUGCCAGACCUGCAGGGACUUCUAUGCAAACAAGAUGCGCCAGCCACCGCCGAACUCGUGACACGCAGUCCCAAGGGUCGCUCAAAGCUCAGACUCAGGUCUGAAACCCACCCACCCGCAAGCCUACCAGCCUUGUGGCCACGCCCCCACCCGGCUGCCACAAGAAUCCAACUACAUAGAACAUGAGCGUGGACUUGGCGUUUGCCAUUAGUGCUUCCGUACUUAAUAUAUUGUUAACAGCCACUGGCUGGCUUUCUACAGUGAGGAGAAAGUAGGCAUGAGUCACAAAGUAACUUCAAUUUCUAGGAUUUCAGGUACCUCGAAGGGAAGCACCUCUGGCAGACAACCGUCAAGAGAGAGACAUCAUUUAGUGUUCUUGUCUUGACUCGCUUUUGACAUUUGAAUUUCCAGUGCUUGGUAUAUCAUGGAGGAAACAUCCCCAAAACGAGACAUGCUAGAAAAGGCUUUAUUCUGAAAGCCGGCGACACCAUGGAGGGAGGGGCAGGUGUUGGUGAGCCUCUGCCCGUGGCUUCUCUGGGGAGGGCCGGGCUGCUUAGCACACGUUUCUCUCCAUCUACCUUCUUGACCACAUGAGAACCAGGACGUUGCCUCCAUGCCCGUCUCUGAGAACAUAGUCUCUAAAUCCUAGGUGUUGCCUUGGAAGUCUCGUGCGUGGAGUGUAAAUCUAUAUAUGCCAGCGAGGACAGCAGUGCCACGCAGUUCAUACCACCCGCAUGGGAAGAAUGUUCCAAGAGAGUCUGGGUUUGGGGAAGCAUCUAAUUUUCAGAGCUCUGCUGUCCACCGUGUAGGGAAACAGAAGGGCCUCUCUUCAAGGUGCUGUGACAUAAGAAACGGUAAUUGCGGUGAUGGGGUUGCUUCCUAAGGCAAAGGUAAGCUUGGGCCAGCUUCACUGGGGCGGAUGGGCACCUGCCCCGCCUUCCGGGAACAUCCACUCUGGCCUGCACUUCCUAAAGCUUUGUACCUUAGAGAUGCUGUACCACAUCCCAGUGGCUUUCUACCGACCGUGGCCAUUUAUCUGAAGGUAAGACGACAUUUGGGACCUCUGAGGACACAAGCCCAGGCCUAGGAUCUGUAGAGCAAGGCCUGACUGCUCUAUCCUGGCACGGAGCAGCCUGAUGUGCCAGGACCAGGGGAGGAACGCCAUCUGGCUGGCACUGCUGCACACCCGCCGAGCCUUCCUGUAGCCCCAGACUUUGUGGUACCCAUUAUCAUCACGCCUGUCAUCAUUGACCCAUCUUCUUGGUGGGGCAAGGAUGAUGCAUGAUGAAGGAAGGUCCUUCCCCCCUGCAGCCCCCUUACGCCUGGCAGCAGACAAGCAGAGUGGCCUCUUUGAGAGCACAGAGGAUGGUAGCACCCUACCUGCAAGGAGGCCGGGCAGGGACCCUAGAUGCCAGGAGGCCUGUUUUGCUCACCAACUUGGUGGGCAUUUCAUGGGUGCUUAUGUUCUAGGACUUUACCGUAAAUAACACCUCCUCCCUGAUUUCAGACGGAAGGUCUCACUUGGACUUCCAUGGGAUCAUCUCCCUGUGCUUCUUGAUUUAUUGGUGCUGUGUUUCUGUGUUUUGUUUUGUUACAUGUCACAACCGUAGAGUUAGCUUAAAUCAGAAAGAAGCCUCUCUGCCUUCUCCACCCUGUCUUACGAGCUGUGUUUUUGUUUUUACUACCCUAGAGGCAGAGAAGCGGUAGGGAUGUCAGGGAAUUUACUCACUUCCACUUGAAUCAACGAGAAGUGUUGAGAAACUUCCGUGGGUGCUCUGUGGAAAGAACCGAGGGUGUCAGGAUGGAGCGGCCCACCCUCGCCCCGCGGCCUGCGCAGACUGCUGUCCUCCCCUUCAGGCCUGGCCACCAGCAGACUCCCAUGAAUUCCCAUUUUCACAAAGCCCUCAAAAUUUUGGGGGCGCUGAGGUUCAAUUUUCUUCAUCCCCAAAUGAACUGUUAAUUCACUGAAAGACAUUUAGACUUUUGCAGCCAAGGAGCAGAGCCGGGCAAGCUCACUAAGGAAGCCUUAGCUUGGUCUCCUGCAUGGGCCCCGGGGCCUCCAGAUAUGCCCACUGUCACCCUGGCAAGGGCCCCACACCCUCAGAAUGAAAAGGAUUGAUUGGGUUAUUGUCAGAUACCCCCAUUAGUUCCCCUAAAGUCUGCAUCUGCAGAGCUCUUUUAGCUCAUCUUUUUGUUGUCGGUGUUGUUUUUUGAGACAGAGUCUCCCUCUGUUGCCCAGGCUGGAGUGCAGUGGCGCGAUCUCAGCUCAUUGAAAGCUCCGCCUCCCGGGUUCAGGCCAUUCUUCUGCCUCACCCUCCCCAGUAGCUGGGACUACAGGCGCCCACCACCACGCCCACCUACUUUUUUGUAUUUUUACUAGAGACGGGGUUUCACCAUGUUAGCCAGGAUGGUCUCGAUCUCCUGACCUCAUGAUCCACCCGCCUCAGCCUUCCAAAGUGCUGGGAUUACAGGAGUGAGCCACCGCGCCCGGCCUUUUAGCUUAUCUUGAAAUCCACCAGCCUACCUUCUGUUCAUGGCACGAGCAGUGAUUUCAGUGAAACCAUCAUAAACAUUCUUGUUCCACUAGAUGCUGAUCACAGCAGUGAUGUUUCUGUGUUAAUACCCUGUACUGUCCCUCGAGUACUGUACCUUUGUGCUUGCACACGUGUCACUAACGCACGUGUUACCAGAGUCUCACGACCCUACGGUGCUAUUUUUAUUGGUGCAAAAUUAAACCCUCUCAGCUGACCGUUGCUGGAUAGGAUCAGAAUGCAGGAAAAGAGCCUCUAUGGCAAUACGAUUGUCCUUUUUUCGUUUCAGAGUCAAAUGUAUCUAUUUUCCAUUCGUUAACUUGCAUUACAUACUGUACCCAUGGAAUUUUUGUUUUACUUUUUGGGGCUGGUUUUGAAAGGAAAAAAAACGGAAGACAAACAUUGGACGCCAUUAUACAUGAAAAUUAUAUAGAAAAAUUAAUCAUUUCAUUGGAAGCAAGUUGAAUAUGUGUAAUAAAAUGUUUUUCCAUAACA